GUGGGGCGGGCGGAGCGCCGCGGGAGGCGGACGAGAUGCGAGCGCGGCCGCGGCCCCGGCCGCUCUGGGCGACUGUGCUGGCGCUGGGGGCGCUGGCGGGCGUUGGCGUAGGAGGGCCCAACAUCUGUACCACGCGAGGUGUGAGCUCCUGCCAGCAGUGCCUGGCUGUGAGCCCCAUGUGUGCCUGGUGCUCUGAUGAGGCCCUGCCUCUGGGCUCACCUCGCUGUGACCUGAAGGAGAAUCUGCUGAAGGAUAACUGUGCCCCAGAAUCCAUCGAGUUCCCAGUGAGUGAGGCCCGAGUACUAGAGGACAGGCCCCUCAGCGACAAGGGCUCUGGAGACAGCUCCCAGGUCACUCAAGUCAGUCCCCAGAGGAUUGCACUCCGGCUCCGGCCAGAUGAUUCGAAGAAUUUCUCCAUCCAAGUGCGGCAGGUGGAGGAUUACCCUGUGGACAUCUACUACUUGAUGGACCUGUCUUACUCCAUGAAGGAUGAUCUGUGGAGCAUCCAGAACCUGGGUACCAAGCUGGCCACCCAGAUGCGAAAGCUCACCAGUAACCUGCGGAUUGGCUUCGGGGCAUUUGUGGACAAGCCUGUGUCACCAUACAUGUAUAUCUCCCCACCAGAGGCCCUCGAAAACCCCUGCUAUGAUAUGAAGACCACCUGCUUGCCCAUGUUUGGCUACAAACACGUGCUGACGCUAACUGACCAGGUGACCCGCUUCAAUGAGGAAGUGAAGAAGCAGAGUGUGUCACGGAACCGAGAUGCCCCAGAGGGUGGCUUUGAUGCCAUCAUGCAGGCUACAGUCUGUGAUGAAAAGAUUGGCUGGAGGAAUGAUGCAUCCCACUUGCUGGUGUUUACCACUGAUGCCAAGACUCAUAUAGCAUUGGACGGAAGGCUGGCAGGCAUUGUCCAGCCUAAUGACGGGCAGUGUCAUGUUGGUAGUGACAAUCAUUACUCUGCCUCCACUACCAUGGAUUAUCCCUCUUUGGGGCUGAUGACUGAGAAGCUAUCCCAGAAAAACAUCAAUUUGAUCUUUGCAGUGACUGAAAAUGUAGUCAAUCUCUAUCAGAACUAUAGUGAGCUCAUCCCAGGGACCACAGUUGGGGUUCUGUCCAUGGAUUCCAGCAAUGUCCUCCAGCUCAUUGUUGAUGCUUAUGGGAAAAUCCGUUCUAAAGUAGAGCUGGAAGUGCGUGACCUCCCUGAAGAGUUGUCUCUAUCCUUCAAUGCCACCUGCCUCAACAAUGAGGUCAUCCCUGGCCUCAAGUCUUGUAUGGGACUCAAGAUUGGAGACACGGUGAGCUUCAGCAUUGAGGCCAAGGUGCGAGGCUGUCCCCAGGAGAAGGAGAAGUCCUUUACCAUAAAGCCCGUGGGCUUCAAGGACAGCCUGAUCGUCCAGGUCACCUUUGAUUGUGACUGUGCCUGCCAGGCCCAAGCUGAACCUAAUAGCCAUCGCUGCAACAAUGGCAAUGGGACCUUUGAGUGUGGGGUAUGCCGUUGUGGGCCUGGCUGGCUGGGAUCCCAGUGUGAGUGCUCAGAGGAGGACUAUCGCCCUUCCCAGCAGGACGAAUGCAGCCCCCGGGAGGGUCAGCCCGUCUGCAGCCAGCGGGGCGAGUGCCUCUGUGGUCAAUGUGUCUGCCACAGCAGUGACUUUGGCAAGAUCACGGGCAAGUACUGCGAGUGUGACGACUUCUCCUGUGUCCGCUACAAGGGGGAGAUGUGCUCAGGCCAUGGCCAGUGCAGCUGUGGGGACUGCCUGUGUGACUCCGACUGGACCGGCUACUACUGCAACUGUACCACGCGUACUGACACCUGCAUGUCCAGCAAUGGGCUGCUGUGCAGCGGCCGCGGCAAGUGUGAAUGUGGCAGCUGUGUCUGUAUCCAGCCGGGCUCCUAUGGGGACACCUGUGAGAAGUGCCCCACCUGCCCAGAUGCCUGCACCUUUAAGAAAGAAUGUGUGGAGUGUAAGAAGUUUGACCGGGGAGCCCUACAUGACGAAAAUACCUGCAACCGUUACUGCCGUGACGAGAUUGAGUCAGUGAAAGAGCUUAAGGACACUGGCAAGGAUGCAGUGAAUUGUACCUAUAAGAAUGAGGAUGACUGUGUCGUCAGAUUCCAGUACUAUGAAGAUUCUAGUGGAAAGUCCAUCCUGUAUGUGGUAGAAGAGCCAGAGUGUCCCAAGGGCCCUGACAUCCUGGUGGUCCUGCUCUCAGUGAUGGGGGCCAUUCUGCUCAUUGGCCUUGCCGCCCUGCUCAUCUGGAAACUCCUCAUCACCAUCCACGACCGAAAAGAAUUCGCUAAAUUUGAGGAAGAACGCGCCAGAGCAAAAUGGGACACAGCCAACAACCCACUGUAUAAAGAGGCCACGUCUACCUUCACCAAUAUCACGUACCGGGGCACUUAAUGAUAAGCAGUCAUCCUCAGAUCAUUAUCAGCCUGUGCCACGAUUGCAGGAGUCCCUGCCAUCAUGUUUACAGAGGACAGUAUUUGUGGGGAGGGAUUUGGGGCUCAGAGUGGGGUAGGUUGGGAGAAUGUCAGUAUGUGGAAGUGUGGGUCUGUGUGUGUGUAUGUGGGGGUCUGUGUGUUUAUGUGUGUGUGUUGUGUGUGGGAGUGUGUAAUUUAAAAUUGUGAUGUGUCCUGAUAAGCUGAGCUCCUUAGCCUUUGUCCCAGAAUGCCUCCUGCAGGGAUUCUUCCUGCUUAGCUUGAGGGUGACUAUGGAGCUGAGCAGGUGUUCUUCAUUACCUCAGUGAGAAGCCAGCUUUCCUCAUCAGGCCAUUGUCCCUGAAGAGAAGGGCAGGGCUGAGGCCUCUCAUUCCAGAGGAAGGGACACCAAGCCUUGGCUCUACCCUGAGUUCAUAAAUUUAUGGUUCUCAGGCCUGACUCUCAGCAGCUAUGGUAGGAACUGCUGGGCUUGGCAGCCCGGGUCAUCUGUACCUCUGCCUCCUUUCCCCUCCCUCAGGCCGAAGGAGGAGUCAGGGAGAGCUGAACUAUUAGAGCUGCCUGUGCCUUUUGCCAUCCCCUCAACCCAGCUAUGGUUCUCUCGCAAGGGAAGUCCUUGCAAGCUAAUUCUUUGACCUGUUGGGAGUGAGGAUGUCUGGGCCACUCAGGGGUCAUUCAUGGCCUGGGGGAUGUACCAGCAUCUCCCAGUUCAUAAUCACAACCCUUCAGAUUUGCCUUAUUGGCAGCUCUACUCUGGAGGUUUGUUUAGAAGAAGUGUGUCACCCUUAGGCCAGCACCAUCUCUUUACCUCCUAAUUCCACACCCUCACUGCUGUAGACAUUUGCUAUGAGCUGGGGAUGUCUCUCAUGACCAAAUGCUUUUCCUCAAAGGGAGAGAGUGCUAUUGUAGAGCCAGAGGUCUGGCCCUAUGCUUCCGGCCUCCUGUCCCUCAUCCAUAGCACCUCCACAUACCUGGCCCUGUGCCUUGGUGUGCUGUAUCCAUCCAUGGGGCUGAUUGUAUUUACCUUCUACCUCUUGGCUGCCUUGUGAAGGAAUUAUUCCCAUGAGUUGGCUGGGAAUAAGUGCCAGGAUGGAAUGAUGGGUCAGUUGUAUCAGCACGUGUGGCCUGUUCUUCUAUGGGUUGGACAACCUCAUUUUAACUCAGUCUUUAAUCUGAGAGGCCACAGUGCAAUUUUAUUUUAUUUUUCUCAUGAUGAGGUUUUCUUAACUUAAAAGAACAUGUAUAUAAACAUGCUUGCAUUAUAUUUGUAAAUUUAUGUGAUGGCAAAGAAGGAGAGCAUAGGAAACCACACAGACUUGGGCAGGGUACAGACACUCCCACUUGGCAUCAUUCACAGCAAGUCACUGGCCAGUGGCUGGAUCUGUGAGGGGCUCUCUCAUGAUAGAAGGCUAUGGGGAUAGAUGUGUGGACACAUUGGACCUUUCCUGAGGAAGAGGGACUGUUCUUUUGUCCCAGAAAAGCAGUGGCUCCAUUGGUGUUGACAUACAUCCAACAUUAAAAGCCACCCCCAAAUGCCCAAGAAAAAAAGAAAGACUUAUCAACAUUUGUUCCAUGAGCAGAAAACUGGAGCUCUGGCCUCAGUGUUACAGCUAAAUAAUCUUUAAUUAAGGCAAGUCACUUUCUUCUUCUUAAAGCUGUUUUCUAGUUUGAGAAAUGAUGGGAUUUUAGCAGCCAGUCUUGAAGGUCUCUUUCAGUAUCAACAUUCUAAGAUGCUGGGACUUACUGUGUCAUCAAAUGUGCGGUUAAGAUUCUCUGGGAUAUUGAUACUGUUUGUGUUUUUAGUUGGGAGAUCUGAGAGACCUGGCUUUGGCAAGAGCAGAUGUCAUUCCAUAUCACCUUUCUCAAUGAAAGUCUCAUUCUAUCCUCUCUCCAAACCCGUUUUCCAACAUUUGUUAAUAGUUACGUCUCUCCUGAUGUAGCACUUAAGCUUCAUUUAGUUAUUAUUUCUUUCUUCACUUUGCACACAUUUGCAUCCACAUAUUAGGGAAGAGGAAUCCAUAAGUAGCUGAAAUAUCUAUUCUGUAUUAUUGUGUUAACAUUGAGAAUAAGCCUUGGAAUUAGAUAUGGGGCAAUGACUGAGCCCUGUCUCACCCAUGGAUUACUCCUUACUGUAGGGAAUGGCAGUAUGGUAGAGGGAUAAAUAGGGGGCGGGGAGGGAUAGUCAUGGAUCCAAGAAGUCCUUAGAAAUAGUGGCAGGGAACAGGUGUGGAAGCUCAUGCCUGUAAUUAUAACCUUCAGCUACUAAGACAGGUGUGGUGGCUCACGCCUGUGAUUAUAAUCUUCAGUUACUAAGACAGAGUCCAUGAGAGUGUUAAUGGGACAUUUUCUUUAGAUAAGAUGUUUUAUAUGAAGAAACUGUAUCAAAGGGGGAAGAAAAUGUAUUUAACAGGUGAAUCAAAUCAGGAAUCUUGUCUGAGCUACUGGAAUGAAGUUCACAGGUCUUGAAGACCAAUAUUAUUUGUCAAUAUGUGGGGAUAACCUGUAGCUGCAUUCAUGAGGUAGCAAAUAGCAGUUUUGGCCUGUGGGGUGAACAGCUAAACAGUGUUCUGGCAUCAGAUAACACGGCACAAAGGGAUUGUGUCUAGCUCUUUUGGAGAAAAUUUAUGUCCAGUCUCAGGAUCUGUGGACAAUAACGGAAAACUUUGAAUAUUCCUGACAAGUUGCCAUAUUAGGAGUCAGUUCUUUACUUCUCUGAGAUUCCCAGGUCAUCCAUGAUUUUUUUUUUAAUUUGAGACAAAGCCUCACUCUUGUUGCCCAAGCUGGAAUGCAAUGGCAAGAUCUCAGUUCACUGCAAUCUCUGCCUCUCAGGUUCAAGCCAUUCUCCUGCCUCAGCCUCCCCAGUAGCCGGGAUUACAGGCACCCGCCACCACACCCGGCUAAUUUUUGUAUUUUUAGUAGAGACGGGGUUUCACCAUGUUGGCCAGGCUGGUCUCGAACUCCUGACCUUAGGCGAUCCACCUUCCUCGGCCUCCCACAGUGCUGGGAUUACAAGUGUGAAGCACUGUGCCCGGCCAGUCAUCCAUGAUUUUAAUGGGGUCCAAAGGCCUCUUUUUCUUUGUUAAGUAUUCCUGGUUGAAAUUUCUUUUCUUUUUUUUUUUUUUUUUGAGACAGAGUCUUGCUCUAUCACCCAGGCUGGAGUGCAGUGGCACGAUCUCUGCUCACUGCAAGCUUCGCCUCCCGGGUUCACGCCAUUCUCCUGCCUCAGCCUCCCGAGUAGCUGGGAUUACAGGCACCUGCCACCACGCCCGGCUAAUUUCUUUUUGUAUUUUUAGUAGAGACGGGGUUUCACGGUGUUAGCCAGGAAGGUCUCGAUCUCCUGACCUCGUGAUCCUCCCGCCUCGGCCUCCCAAAGUGCUGGGAUUACAGGCGUGAGCCACUGCCCCCGGCUGUGGUUGAAAUUUCUUAAGUGCCUUCCUCACUUCCUAACCACCUUCUCUGUUUGGGUUUGUGCAACAGUAAAUUAAAUGUACUUUCCAAAAAGAA